AAGUGGAGACACGUGCUUUGGCCUGUUGGAGGGGAAACCCGCUCUCGCCUCCUGGUGGUCGCCGACUCGCAGUCCGCAGGAUGACUCAGGGCAGCCCUGACCACAGUUCCGCCGCCAUCGGCCCUAGCCUGCGGAAUUGGGCUCGCCCCGGGACGAUAACAGAGCUCUGCCGGGGGCUGGAGGCACUGACCGGGUGACCAGAGACCCAGAGACCAGACCCCCUCCACGGCGCCCGGGAUUUCGGGGACGGCUUCUCCCAUCGCAAGUUUCAACAGAAAAUGAGAAAUAUCCCCCGACGAUUGGCUGAAAACAUGCAGCAACCACUAUUUUCUUCCUGCCCCUCGUUGAUGAGAGCAUUCGAAGUGACCUCAGCAGGGCAUCCAGGUCAGUUUCUGGAAGACUUGUGUGUGUGAUGAAUGAAUAUCUGGUUUUGUCUCUGCUGGGCCUGUGUGCCUGGAAAGGAAUUGUUUUGGCCUAGGAUCAUCCAGCUAGACUUCGGGCUCCUUGAGGAUAUUCAGUUUUGUAUGUUUGAAUAUCCUCUCACCAUGUUCAGCAUAAAGUACCAUUCUUAAUGAUUAUCCUCAACAAGACAGGUGUGAGAGGGUUGCUGUUGUAUUGCAAUCAUGGUGCAGAAAUACCAGUCCCCAGUGAGGGUGUACAAAUACCCCUUUGAAUUAAUUAUGGCUGCCUAUGAAAGGAGGUUCCCUACAUGUCCUUUGAUUCCGAUGUUCGUGGGCAGUGACACUGUGAAUGAAUUCAAGAGCGAAGAUGGGGCUAUUCAUGUCAUUGAAAGGCGCUGCAAGCUGGAUGUAGAUGCACCCAGACUGCUGAAGAAGAUUGCAGGAGUUGAUUAUGUUUAUUUUGUCCAGAAAAACUCACUGAAUUCUCGGGAACGUACUUUGCACAUUGAGGCUUAUAAUGAAACGUUUUCCAAUCGGGUCAUCAUUAAUGAGCAUUGCUGCUACACCGUUCACCCUGAAAAUGAAGAUUGGACCUGUUUUGAACAGUCUGCAAGUUUAGAUAUUAAAUCUUUCUUUGGUUUUGAAAGUACAGUGGAAAAAAUUGCAAUGAAACAAUAUACCAGCAACAUUAAAAAAGGAAAGGAAAUCAUCGAAUACUACCUUCGCCAAUUAGAAGAAGAAGGCAUAACCUUUGUGCCCCGUUGGAGUCCGCCUUCCAUCACGACCUCUUCAGAGACAUCUUCAUCAUCCUCCAAGAAACAAGCAGCGUCCAUGGCCGUCGUCAUCCCAGAAGCUGCCCUCAAGGAGGGGCUGAGUGGUGAUGCCCUCAGCAGCCCCAGCGCACCUGAGCCCGUGGUGGGCACCCCUGACGACAAACUAGAUGCCGACUACAUCAAGAGAUACCUGGGCGAUUUGACUCCGCUGCAGGAGAGCUGCCUCAUUAGACUUCGCCAGUGGCUCCAGGAGACCCACAAGGGCAAAAUUCCAAAAGAUGAGCAUAUUCUUCGGUUCCUCCGUGCACGGGAUUUUAAUAUUGACAAAGCCAGAGAGAUCAUGUGUCAGUCUUUGACGUGGAGAAAGCAGCAUCAGGUAGACUACAUUCUUGAAACCUGGACCCCUCCUCAGGUCCUUCAGGAUUACUACGCGGGAGGCUGGCAUCAUCACGACAAAGAUGGGCGGCCCCUCUACGUGCUCAGGCUGGGGCAGAUGGACACCAAAGGCUUGGUGAGAGCGCUCGGGGAGGAAGCCCUGCUGAGAUACGUUCUCUCCAUAAAUGAAGAAGGGCUAAGGCGAUGCGAAGAGAAUACAAAAGUCUUUGGUCGGCCUAUCAGCUCAUGGACCUGCCUGGUGGACUUGGAAGGGCUGAACAUGCGCCACUUGUGGAGACCUGGUGUGAAAGCGCUGCUGCGGAUCAUCGAGGUGGUGGAGGCCAACUACCCUGAGACACUGGGCCGCCUUCUCAUCCUGCGGGCGCCCAGGGUAUUUCCUGUGCUCUGGACGCUGGUUAGUCCGUUCAUUGAUGACAACACCAGAAGGAAGUUCCUCAUUUAUGCAGGAAAUGACUACCAGGGUCCUGGAGGCCUGCUGGAUUACAUCGACAAAGAGAUUAUUCCAGAUUUCCUGAGUGGGGAGUGCAUGUGCGAAGUGCCAGAGGGUGGACUGGUCCCCAAAUCUCUGUACCGGACUGCAGAGGAGCUGGAGAACGAAGACCUGAAGCUCUGGACUGAGACCAUCUACCAGUCUGCAAGCGUCUUCAAAGGAGCCCCACAUGAGAUUCUCAUUCAGAUUGUGGAUGCCUCGUCAGUCAUCACUUGGGAUUUCGACGUGUGCAAAGGGGACAUUGUGUUUAACAUCUAUCACUCCAAGAGGUCGCCACAACCACCCAAAAAGGACUCCCUGGGAGCCCACAGCAUCACCUCUCCGGGUGGGAACAAUGUGCAGCUCAUAGACAAAGUCUGGCAGCUGGGCCGCGACUACAGCAUGGUGGAGUCGCCUCUGAUCUGCAAAGAAGGAGAAAGCGUGCAGGGUUCCCAUGUGACCAGGUGGCCGGGCUUCUACAUCCUGCAGUGGAAAUUCCACAGCAUGCCUGCGUGCGCCGCCAGCAGCCUUCCCCGGGUGGACGACGUGCUUGCGUCCCUGCAGGUCUCUUCGCACAAGUGUAAAGUGAUGUACUACACCGAGGUGAUCGGCUCGGAGGAUUUCAGAGGUUCCAUGACGAGCCUGGAGUCCAGCCACAGCGGCUUCUCCCAGCUGAGUGCCGCCACCACCUCCUCCAGCCAGUCCCACUCCAGCUCCAUGAUCUCCAGGUAGUGCCGCGCUGCCUGCACCUAGUGUGCAGAGGGGACGGCCGCCCCUCCUCGGACAGCCAGCUGCACCCGCCCACCCAGCGGCGACAUUGUACAGACUCCUCUCACCUCUAGAUAGCAAAUAGCUCUCAGAUGGUAAACGUAGUCGUUUGAUCCCAAAACUACCUUGGCAGGUAGUUUUAACUCUGAUCCUAACUUAACUCAAUAGCCAUAGAUUUUGUAUACGUUGUGCACAAAAUCCAACCAGAGCGCAAGGGCUCUCUUGAAAGAAAAGUAGUUUCUGUACCAAUUAAAGGAUUGACGUGGUCUCAGAUAUUGAUGCAAAAAAUUUUUCCAACGAACUCCGCAUUGUCCAUUAGUGAAUGAAUUCCUGUGACAUCCUCCAGAGAUGGCCCCUCCUCACCUGGGACGGAAGCUGCCAGCUCGCUUCCCCCAAGCUGCCUCAUGGCCCGCACGCCGCCUCACGGCCCCCAUGCUUCCCGCCAGUCAAGAUGGUCUGUGGACUUAGGGCCAGCCCUUGAGGUCCUUAUCCUCUGAGGAUUCAGAGGUUGCCUGCGGAGUACCUUGUCCCAGGGCCAGACACACCCACACCACCCACUGUCCUGCAGUGGGGCCGGGGGCUCAGGAGGGGCUCUCAGGGACUCCUGGUGACUCCAGGAAAAUGCUGCCAUCGUUAAACAUUACUUUCUCUUUCCUCCUUUUCAAAUCUUUUUGAUACUUUUUAGAGCAGGAUUUUUCUGUAUGUGAACUUGGGUGGGGGGGUUCUUCCCGUUUCCUUCCGUGCGUCGCCCCUCUCACCUGCAGUCAGCUCCCAGCCCAGUGUAGGCCAUCUCCUCUGUGCCCUCUGGUGGCUCAUUGUCCUCAGAGCCCAGACAGUUCCAGCCACUAGGAGGCCGUCUUGGAACCAGCAAGUCGCAUUUGCCACUUGACACUGUCCAUGGGGUUUUAUUAGUAGCUAAGCAGCAGCUCUCGCAUCCACUUCAGGGUGGCGUGUGGCAUGUAGGAGUCCUGCUUCUUUGUACAUGGGAAUUGUGGACUCAUGCGUGUGUGUGUGUGCAUGUGCUGUGUGUGUGCAUGUGUGCAUGACGGUGGGGGUGCUGGGGGGACGGGGUGAGUGGAAACUUAGUUUGAGUAAUGAAGGAAUCUUCACAGAAGCAAAUCAGAAUAUGGGAUUUGUUUGCCUUUUACAUUUUGUUUAAUUCCUGAUUUUAAAGCCUGCUCUAUCUGGUACAGGCCCUUAUUUUUUCAGCUUUUUAUGGGAAAAGCAGGUUAUUUGAGAAUCUGUCCAGAAGUUGCAUAGGGGAUGGCCUCCACGAUAAGGACAUGCAACACGUGUUUCUGUGUGCAGCAGAGGCCGUGUUUUUCAUGCCAAACCCCACGCGGCUGUCAACUGUGUGCGUGGUAGGCAUGGAGAUCCUGGUUGUGCCGUCUCAGCUCCGCUCUGAAGGCACUGUGUGGGUGCUGCGUGACUGGAGAGCUGUGUGGAGGCCAUGUGUGCCCCGUGCAGGGAUCAGGAGGGCGGGGGAGGGACCGAGCAGCCCUCUUGCCCGGUCGGGUCAGCCCUAGUGGCUGCCUGCACACUGUAGACGUCCCAGGGCCUGUGCUGUGAUCACCUGCCUUUGGACCACAUUUGUGUUUGCUCUUAGAGAUCGAGCUCCUCAGUGGUACCUGAAGCCUUUGCUUCCGGAAAGCGCGGUAGGGUUCGUAGGUAGGGCUAGUAGGUAGGGUUAGUAGGUAGGGCUAGUAGGUAGGGCUAGUAGGUAGGGUUCGUAGGUAGGGUUCGUAGGUAGGGCUGGUAGGUAGGGUUAGUAGGUAGGGCUAGUAGGUAGGGUUAGUAGGUAGGGUUCGUAGGUAGGGUUCGUAGGUAGGGUUCGUAGGUAGGGCUAGUAGGUAGGGUUAGUAGGUAGGGUUCGUAGGUAGGGUUCGUAGGUAGGGUUAGGUAGGGUUCGUAGGUAGGGUUAGUAGGUAGGGCUAGUAGGUAGGGUUCGUAGGUAGGGUUCGUAGGUAGGGCUAGUAGGUAGGGUUAGUAGGUAGGGCUAGUAGGUAGGGCUAGUAGGUAGGGUUAGUAGGUAGGGCUAGUAGGUAGGGUUCGUAGGUAGGGUUAGUAGGUAGGGCUAGUAGGUAGGGUUCGUAGGUAGGGUUCGUAGGUAGGGCUAGUAGGUAGGGUUAGUAGGUAGGGCUAGUAGGUAGGGCUAGUAGGUAGGGUUCGUAGGUAGGGUUCGUAGGUAGGGUUCGUAGGUAGGGUUCGUAGGUAGGGUUAGUAGGUAGGGUUCGUAGGUAGGGCUAGUAGGUAGGGCUAGUAGGUAGGGCUAGUAGGUAGGGUUAGUAGGUAGGGCUAGUAGGUAGGGCUAGUAGGUAGGGCUAGUAGGUAGGGCUAGUAGGUAGGGUUCGUAGGUAGGGUUCGUAGGUAGGGUUCGUAGGUAGGGUUAGUAGCGCGUCUGUGCUGCUUCCACCUGGUGCUUCCUGUUCCCAAAUCACAAGGGCCUGAAGGUGGUCCCUGCUUUCUCUUUCUCUUUCUCUGUGUCUCAGAUGGCGAUUUUGCUGACAGCUGCCAAGAAAAUGCUUCACUCAACAGUCCUCAUGUGCCCAGAGAUGUUUAUAGAACUGUUUGAAUUGCAGCCAUCCCCUGCCCCCUCCCAGGCUGAAGAUCUGUUCUUUUUAAGUUGAUUCGGGAGUGGCAUUCUUUUAUACCCAAAGACUGUAGUGCAUCUUGAAGAGCUCAAAGCACAUGACCGCACAAAUGCUUACAGGGUUUCCUCCCGAGUAAUCCAAUCUCACUCCCCUUGUAAGGGAAUUCUGGGGCAGCUAUGGUUUGAGUAUGCAGUUUGCAUCGUGUUUCUACCUUUAGUACCUUGCCACUCUUUUAAAACGCUGCUGUCAUUUCCCAUUUCUUAGUACUAAUGAUUCUUUGAUUCUCCCUCUAUUAUGUCUUAAUUCACUUUCCUUCCUAAAUUUGUUAUUUGCAUAUCAAAUUCUGUAAAUGUUUUGUAAACAUAUUACCUCACUUGGUAAUACAAUACUGAUAGUCUUUAAAAGAUUUUUUUAUUGUUAUCAAUAAUAAAUGUGAACUAUUUAAAGAAAA